AGUUCCUGUGAGCGUCGGCGUCUUCUGGGCCUGUGGAGUUUCUUGGACAGGGGCCGCGGGGCUCCAGGACGGCGCCCUUAGCGACACCAUGGCCCGAAAUGCAGAAAAGGCCAUGACGGCCUUAGCAAGAUUUCGCCAGGCUCAGCUGGAAGAGGGAAAAGUGAAGGAACGAAGACCCUUUCUGGCCUCAGAAUGUACUGAACUGCCUAAAGCUGAGAAGUGGAGACGACAGAUCAUUGGAGAGAUCUCUAAAAAAGUGGCUCAGAUUCAGAAUGCUGGUUUAGGUGAAUUUCGAAUUCGUGACCUGAAUGAUGAAAUUAACAAGCUGCUAAGGGAGAAAGGACACUGGGAGGUCCGGAUAAAGGAGCUGGGAGGUCCUGAUUAUGGAAAAGUUGGCCCUAAAAUGCUGGAUCAUGAAGGAAAAGAAGUCCCAGGAAACCGAGGUUACAAGUACUUUGGAGCAGCAAAAGAUUUGCCUGGUGUUAGAGAGCUGUUUGAAAAAGAACGCCAGGUGCGGUGGCUCAUGCCUGUAAUCCCAGCACUUUGGGAGGCUGAGGCGGGCGGAUCACAAGCUCUUCCUCCUCCCAGAAAGACACGUGCUGAGCUCAUGAAGGCAAUCGAUUUUGAGUACUAUGGUUACCUAGAUGAAGAUGAUGGUGUUAUUGUGCCUUUGGAACAGGAAUAUGAAAAGAAACUCAGAGCCGAGUUAGUGGAAAAGUGGAAAGCAGAGAGAGAGGCUCGGCUGGCAAGAGGAGAAAAGGAAGAGGAGGAGGAAGAGGAGGAAGAGAUCAACAUCUAUGCAGUCACCGAGGAGGAGUCGGACGAGGAAGGCAGCCAGGAGAAAGGAGGGGACGACAGCCAGCAGAAGUUCAUUGCUCACGUCCCUGUUCCCUCGCAGCAAGAGAUUGAGGAGGCACUGGUGCGAAGGAAGAAAAUGGAACUCCUCCAGAAGUAUGCAAGCGAGACCCUGCAGGCCCAAAGUGAAGAAGCCAGAAGGCUCCUGGGGUAUUAGGACCCAGCUGGGGCUCUCCUUGGAGUUCUUCCAUCCCCCAGUGGUACCUCAGGACCCAGGGCUGCAGACACAGGCUGGUGCUGCAAGGGCUCCUGCCCCAUUCUCAGCCUUCCUUCCCUCUCCUUGUCUCAUGUUGACCGGAGGGUAGGGGUCUGUCCCUGGUCUUCCUGGUAGGUUUUGUACACAUAUUUUGCUACUGUGUGGAUCCAUUUAUUUUUAUUGUGGAGUGUAUACAACAGGUUGCGAACUGGCUGCCUGUGUCUUAUUUUGACUUGCACUGCCAUUUUGAGGGGAGAAGAAUCAAUUAGUGGCAAACAUUUAAAAAUGCAAUUUUUUGCAGACCAAAGUAUAAUUUUAAAAAAUGCAAAUUUUCUAAAAGACACAUCUCUUGAAAAAUGAGAUGAUGUGGCCAGGCGCAGUGGCUCACGCCUGUAACCCCAGCACUUUGGGAGGCCGAGGCGGGCGGGUCACGAGGUCAAGAGAUGGAGACCAUCCUGGCCAACAUGGUGAAACCCCAUGUCUACUAAAAAUACAAAAAAAUUAGCUGGGCGUACUGGCAUGCACCUGUAGUCCCAGCUGCUUGGGAGGCUGAGGCAGGAGAAUCACUUGAACCCGAGAGGUGGAGGUUGAAGUGAGCCAAGAUCGUGCCAUUGCACUCCAGCCUGGCGACAGAGUGAGACUCUGUCCCAAAAAAAAAAAAAAAAAAAGAUGCACGCAACCCACAAGUCAAUGACCAGGUCCCUCUGUGUUGGUUGCUGCUCUGGGCUCUCCGUUAGCCCCCCUCCACCUGCUCCACUCGCUCCUGCCUGGGUGGCAGGAAUUUGAGUUUGCUAUUCCUGUUUUAUAACCUGUUCUGCAGAAACCUAUUUUUAUUAAAGAUUUUUAUAAGAAAGGGAAACCUCCAUGUCUUCAGCUUGUUCCCUGGGCCAACGGCUCUGAGGUGACAGUGGCAUUAGGAUGUGACCAGUCACUAAGGGGCACUGCCUUCCUGCAGGGGAGUCCCUGAAGCCCCAGCCCCAAGUGUGGCAAAGACAGGACCAGAUCCCAGGAGUCUAGGUGGGAGUGAGCCGACCCACCAUGGCGUCCGUGGCCACAGCUGUAGACAGGGCUCCUUGCAGUGGGCUGCACCGUGGCCUGCUGAAAGCACACAGUGGACACGAGCUGAGUCCAGAGCUUCCUCUGAACUGGGGCUUAGCUCUCCAGUGGGGAACCAUGGUCAGCGGCUGUAGCCCCUGGGCAAGAUGGUGCCUGGCUUCCUGCCCUCUGCAGGGUCAUGGGAGUGUCUGGGAACUCAGGGUCAGGGCCAGAUGGCUGUUCCUGGGGCCUGGGGCUCCAGCUCAGGCUGUUUGGGAAUAGGAGGAACUCUUGGCUUGGAGAAGCCCAUCACACAGCGGGAGGCCUGGGAUGGUUGGUCUGCGGGGAGCAGCUCAGACUGGGGGUGGCAGAGCCGUGUGUGGCUGUGUGUGGCCAAGUCGGGAGAGUGGCCAGUGCUGGGCCCUCUCUAAGGAGCCCGAGGGCCACAAGGACUGUGGAAAAGGUCUGAGUGAGGGAGUCGGGAGCUAGUGGCUAAGGGACUUGCUUGAGGACGCUCCGUGCGGCCACAAGGAGAGGCCCAGGCAGGACCAGGUCAGGAGGAGGCUGGGGCAGAGGCCCUGGCAGGAGGUGGGUGGGCUUGGUGGGGAUGGGAGUAGCCAGGGUGUAGGUGAGGAUGGGGAAGGGGCCCCCCUGCCUCCUGGCUUCCCUGAGGGCUGGGCUGGCCAAUCCCAGCCCUCAGUCAAGCCCGGAGGCAAAUGUGUGCAGGGAGGAGAGGUGUCCAGGUUGAAGCUUUGGGAGCCCUUGGAGGCAGCAAGGCAGACUCGCCUCUGGGACCCAGCACCCAGCUUGGGCCUGCAGGUGGGGACUCAGGAGUGAAUAUCGUGGGGGCUUUGAGCAAGACCCUCUGGGCCCAGCCUCACCUUCCAUACUUUGAAGUCAAGGAGUGGACCUGUGCUGUCUCAGUUUGCUCUGGGGUCUGGGCAGUCCUGUGGUUUGGGCAGAGGCCUCAGAGGGCCCUAGGGACAGACUGACCCAGGUCUGAGCCUCUUGGGAGCGUGCGGAUGGCCGGCCUCAGACAGGCCUGGUUGUGGGUUUGUCUUCCAAGGGGCACACGCGCACUCUGGUGCUUCCUGGCAUUCAGAAGAGAAUGGGGAAUCCAGACAUCAGGCCUUCCUUCUCCCUGGGAAGGAUGGCAGGUGCUUGGAGCCAGGCCUGUCUUGAGAGCCAGGGCUCUGGGUCUUCCUCCUCCAGUGCCCUGUUCCACGCCUUCAGUGCACAAAGCACUCCCCUCCUGGGAUCUCUUCAGGGAUCCCCGGGAUGCAAACUGGCCAGGGAUUAGAAUUCCACAUUUGAGCAAACAGACUGAGAGUGGAGAAGCACCCAGCUGGACAUCCUCUAGGUGUUCCUGGCAGAGGCCCUUGCUACUUGUCUGUGCCCAAAGGCCCUAGAGGGUCCUAGAUGUGGGACAAGGUCUCAGCAGGGCUCCAGUCCCAGGCCUGGAAACAGCUGGGGGUGGGGGAAGCUGGCUGGGUGGGUGUGGUUAUCUUUUCCCAGCUUGUGGCUCCGAGGUGACAGAACCAAUCUCAGGAGGCUUUGUUUGGUUAAUAAAAUCUACUGAAUGGUUUAUUUUA